GACAUCACCAAGGGCCUGGCACCAGGUGCCCAGUCUUCCAGUUGCGAGGGCAAGCAAACCCGUCAUGAGCAACUCCCUUCCCCAUCUCUGCUCACCAUGUGGACGCUGAAAUCGUCCCUGGUCCUGCUUCUGUGCCUCACCUGCAGCUAUGCCUUUAUGUUCUCUUCUCUGAGACAGAAAACUAGCGAACCCCAGGGGAAGGUGCCGUGUGGAGAGCACUUUCGGAUUCGGCAGAACCUACCAGAGCACACCCAAGGCUGGCUUGGGAGCAAAUGGCUCUGGCUUUUGUUUGCUGUUGUGCCGUUUGUGAUACUGCAGUGUCAAAGAGACAGUGAGAAGAAUAAGGAGCAGAGUCCUCCUGGCCUUCGAGGCUUCCCAUUUCGCACUCCACUAAAGAAAAAUCAAAAUGCUUCUCUUUACAAAGACUGUGUAUUCAAUACCUUAAACGAACUUGAAGUGGAGCUUUUGAAAUUUGUGUCCGAAGUGCAGAAUCUUAAAGGUGCCAUGGCAACAGGCAGUGGCAGUAACCUCAAGCUUCGAAGGUCAGAGAUGCCUGCAGAUCCAUACCAUGUCACAAUCUGUAAAAUAUGGGGAGAAGAAAGCUCUAGCUGAAUGGAUUUGUGUGUCAGGAGAGAAAAAAGUUGAGUGUUGACAAACUGUAUGCAAACUAAUAAAACUAUUCUGAAGAAAAGAA